GAAAUGGGGAAACAGGGCGUUUGGACAGGAGCCCAACUUUUCUGUCGGCCUGGGUGGACAGCGCCUAAAAGCCUCAGGCAGAUGAGUUUCCCACCGUGAUAGGCGUUCUUCACCUUGUCACUGUCUUCCUGUUGUAACUGGUUUGGGAGUUCCACGGUUUCGAAGUCCUUAACUCUACUAGCCUAGUAUGAUUUUCUACUACUCACUACUACCAACCUUUUGCUUUCAUUUUAUUGUCAUUCACCACCCCCCACCUCUCCCACUUUCUACUGACUGUACUGGCCCGGCCUGAAAAGCCGACAGGACAGAUGCAUCCUGGGAAAAGUGGGAGGGCCUUCCAGGAGAGGCUGGGUUCCUGGGUUCUCUUUGGGAACCAAGAUCGAGGUGUUUGGCAGGGGGAUCAUUUCGGAAACAACUUUGCUUUCUCCCCCUUGGCUUGUUGCAAGUGCAUGUUGGCGAGGCGGGAAUCCCCCAAAGAGGCCUUGUGGUUUCCUGUAGCAGUGACUGUUGGAAUCGAAGCCUCUUAAAAUGGCAGAUGACUUGGACUUCGAGACAGGAGAUGCAGGGGCCUCAGCCACCUUCCCAAUGCAGUGCUCAGCAUUACGUAAGAAUGGCUUUGUGGUGCUCAAAGGCCGGCCAUGUAAGAUCGUCGAGAUGUCUACUUCGAAGACUGGCAAGCACGGCCACGCCAAGGUUAGAAUUUCACCUCCGCAUCUUGCCUUCCCCAUGCCUCCAGUAUCUUUGGCGCUCCCAGCAGCAAGCUGCCAACAGUGCUGACUUUCCUUUAACUCUGCUUUUACUGUCUGAUUGUUUUUGUUUAGCGCUCAGCCUUCAUACCCAUUCAGACAACUACACCUGCUCCCCAGUCUUCAGCCUCUUCUGUGGUUACCCUUCUGUCCCCGCAUCAUUCUCUGGCAGUCCCUCCGUUUCUCCAGCUUUGUGCCAAUCUCUUCAAUUCAUAGGCCUUUAUGCUCUAGCUAUUCAGUUGCUCCUUCCUUAUUCUUGGUUUUCACUUUUUCUUUCUUCCCUUGAGCCGUUGUUAAGUGGUUGCUUCCAUCACGUUGCCCAGGGUUUCUCCAAUUCUACGCCUUCCCCUGGAGGGACUCCUGCGUCAAUUCUGAGCUUUCAGGUCACCUUGCUGCUUCGUUCCCCAGUUCUAGCUUUCCCUUUGGAACUCUGACGCAGGAUCAAACUGCCCCUACCUGCCCCAUCCCACUCUCCUUGGGUUCCUUGAGCCUCCAUGCUUUCAUGGGUUUUAACAUUCUUGCUAGCACUUCCCUCAUCACCUCAGACUUUUCCUGUCUCUUUAGAAUUUCAACCUGAUUCGUUCUUGUUGAAUUUCUUGUGGUGUUUUUCCUUAAUCAGUUUUUCCAUCUUUUGACUUGACAUUGAUCUUGGAUUAUUCUCUAGUGUCUGGAUCCCUCUCUGUGCUCUUCUGGCUUCCUUAUUUUCUAGCUACAUAGUUAUUUCUGAUCUCCCUGCAAGUCCUUUUCUUCAGCUCUUUCACAUUUCUUAGUUUCUUAUCCUUUCCCUUCUACCUUCCUUAUUCCCCAGUUUCUCAGCUCCUUCUCCUGGUGUCCGGAAAACUCUUCGAAACUUUUACUCAGACUCCUCCCACUCCCCUAGACUCUUAGCAUCUUAUCUUUUAUCAAGGUAACUGUCUUCUCCAAGCCUGCCAUGCAGUUUUCUAUUGUGCUGUCAACCCCAAUCUCAACGGUGGUUUUUUAGCCUCUGUUUUUUUUCUUUAAGAGGCUUUACUGUUUCUUGAGUUGACUGGUUCAAUUCCAACACUCCAGUCUUUGCCCCAACAAUGUAAUUCUGACUUCCCUCAUCAGGCAAGGUCAAUUUGAGCCUUUAUUUCCUCCGUUUUAGAGUUUGGUUGGGUUUCUCUUUGUGAUGCAUAC